AGUGAGCGGCGGCGGCUGCGCGGCGGCAGCGGCAGAAAGCGUAGCUGCUUUGCUGUAGUCCACGCCCCCUUGCCGCUCCGGUGACAGUCUCUGCGGAAAGUCACGUUUGUGAUUUCGGGAGAGCACAGAACGGGACGACGGCGCUCUUGCUGGGUCAUCUGGGCCAGGUGACGAAGAAACAGUUUCCUGGUGAAGCAGUCCCUCACCCCUAGUCAGCCCACACCCCUAGGGCCUAAAGAUGCUGAGGUCUGUAUGGAAUUUUCUGAAACGCCACAAAAAGAAAUGCAUCUUCCUGGGCACGGUCCUUGGAGGAGUAUAUAUUCUGGGGAAAUAUGGACAGAAGAAAAUCAGAGAAAUACAGGAAAGGGAGGCUGCAGAAUACAUUGCCCAAGCACGACGACAAUAUCAUUUUGAAAGUAACCAGAGGACUUGCAAUAUGACAGUGCUGUCCAUGCUUCCAACACUGAGAGAGGCCUUAAUGCAGCAACUGAAUUCCGAGAGCCUCACAGCUCUGCUAAAAAACAGGCCUUCAAACAAGCUAGAAAUAUGGGAGGAUCUGAAGAUAAUAAGUUUCACAAGAAGUACUGUGGCUGUAUACAGUACCUGUAUGCUGGUUGUUCUUUUGCGGGUCCAGUUAAACAUAAUUGGUGGAUAUAUUUACCUGGAUAAUGCAGCAGUUGGCAAAAAUGGCACUACAAUUCUUGCUCCCCCAGAUGUCCAACAGCAGUAUUUAUCAAGUAUUCAGCACCUACUUGGAGAUGGCCUGACAGAAUUGAUCACUGUCAUUAAACAAGCUGUGCAGAAGGUUUUAGGAAGUGUUUCUCUUAAACAUUCUUUGUCCCUUUUGGACUUGGAGCAAAAACUAAAAGAAAUCAGAAAUCUCGUUGAGCAGCAUAAGUCUUCUUCUUGGAUUAAUAAAGAUGGAUCCAAACCUUUAUUAUGCCAUUAUAUGAUGCCAGAUGAAGAAACUCCAUUAGCAGUGCAGGCCUGUGGACUUUCUCCUCGAGACAUUACCACUAUUAAACUUCUCAAUGAAACUAGAGACAUGUUGGAAAGCCCAGAUUUUAGUACAGUUUUGAAUACCUGUUUAAACCGAGGUUUUAGUAGACUUCUAGACAAUAUGGCUGAGUUCUUUCGACCUACUGAACAGGACCUGCAACAUGGUAACUCUAUGAAUAGUCUUUCCAGUGUCAGCCUGCCUUUAGCUAAGAUAAUUCCAAUAGUAAACGGACAGAUCCAUUCAGUUUGCAGUGAAACACCUAGUCAUUUUGUUCAGGAUCUGUUGACAAUGGAGCAAGUGAAAGACUUUGCUGCUAAUGUGUAUGAAGCUUUUAGUACCCCUCAGCAACUGGAGAAAUGAUUUUUCCUUCAAGAAAAACUACAGUGGGAUUCAUUUACUUUUUAAAAUACACUGGGUAAAUCACCUAUACUUAGAGUAACAGUUUGUUAUCAAAAUGCCUGAUAAAAUAUAUUCUUAAUAAAAGUCUUCAUUUCAUAAUGAAAUCAAUUUAUUUGGCAUCUUAAUAUAUUUUUUUAGAUUCAUCAACAGACCAGUUUUUGUGGGCAUAUAUAUAUACACGUGCAAAUAUCAGAAUUGUUAAUAAUUUGUUACACAUGGACAUUUGUUCCAAACUGACUAAAAAUCAAUAUAGAUAUUUUAUAUACAUAUAUAUAUAUAAAAAUACAAAAUUCAGUGUACUUUACCAUAUUAAUACUGAGGAAAAAUCUGUUGGAGACAUAGGUCUAGGAUGUGUGAAGUUUGGAAAAAUAUGCUAUUUAAUUAUAAUGUUCCCUAGACUGCUGUAAACAGAAGUGAAUCAGACUUUUCUCCAGCUACCUUUCAAAAUAAUAAAUUAUUUGUCUCAAAUAUACCUUGAUGGAGGACUUUUUUAUUCUUAUGGAAAUAGUGAAUUCCAACAACUAUGAUGAACUAUGUUCUUUGCUAUUUCUUCACUAUAUUUUUUAAGGUUUUAUUAAAAAGCCUUAGAAAGUUACAUAUUGGUUUAGAGGCUAAAAUUGUGUUGAUGCUGUUUACUCACCUAAUUACAUAGUUUUAAUCAUUUGUACAUAAUUUUAAAAACUUACUUUGUAUUGAUUUUGAAUACAGUGAAAAUCUUAUUGCAAUAAACUAUUUUAGUAAAAUAUUAUUUUGUUGAGUUAAUAUUUUUCAGCUAUUAAUUUACUUAUCCCAUAGCAUUUUUGUUAUUAUUUCGGAAGAGAGAGCAUGCUAGUUUAAGUUUCAUUUUAAUUGGUCGUGUACUUGGUGCUUUUUUGUUGUUGUUAACUUGUUCAUUUAGUAAAAAGCAAAUAGCUUUACUUUCUGAAAAAGAAAUAAUUCAUUAUCUCUAGUAAUACAUCUGUAAUUCUUCAUUUAGAAGGGUAAUUAGGGCAAAAGUAAAUAAAUCAUUAUAUAUCAUUAGUAUGUUGACAUAUAUUUUCAGUAACAUUGUUUUAUGUUCCUCCAGCGUAACAUGUAGCUGAACAGUAGAAGGUAGAAAAUAAAUUAUGACAUCUCUUCUAAGGCCUGGCUAGGCCUGAAGCUCACUGCCAGGGAGUUUGUGUCUAGAAUGUUUUUAAAAAUAGGUAGUGGAGCCAUAGCCCUCACCAUAGACACCUCUGAGCCCACUGGCAUUGUCUCUGAGCAGAAGAUGGCUGUGCCACUCACAUAUGCUAAUCUUGGCAAAUCUGCCAAGCAUGUCUUCACCAAGGGAUAUGGAUUUGGCUUAAUAAAACCUGAUUUGAAAACAAAA